GUGCCCCGCGCUCCGCGCCCCCUUCUCUUUCAGCCUCGGGCACGGGGGAGGCUCGGCGGACCUGCUGAUUGGGAACCGAUAUGGCGGCGACUCUGGGCAGCGGGGAGCGCUGGACGGAAGCUUACAUUGACGCAGUUAGAAGAAACAAAUACCCAGAAGACACACCUCCUGAGAGUCAUGACCCCUGUGGCUGCUGUAACUGCAUGAAGGCACAAAAGGAAAAGAAGUCUGAGAAUGAGUGGACUCAGACCCGGCAGGGUGAGGGGAACUCCACGUAUAGUGAGGAACAGCUGCUUGGGGUACAAAGGAUCAAGAAAUGCAGAAAUUACUAUGAAAUUCUGGGAGUUUCUCGAGAUGCUAGUGACGAAGAGCUUAAGAAAGCUUACAGAAAACUCGCCCUGAAAUUUCACCCUGACAAGAACUGUGCUCCUGGAGCAACAGAUGCUUUCAAAGCAAUAGGAAAUGCAUUUGCAGUCCUGAGCAAUCCUGAUAAGAGACUUCGCUAUGAUGAAUACGGAGAUGAACAGGUGACUUUCACUGCCCCUCGAGCCAGACCUUAUAAUUAUUACAGGGAUUUUGAAGCUGACAUCACUCCAGAAGAGCUGUUCAACGUCUUCUUUGGAGGACAUUUUCCUACAGGAAAUAUUCAUAUGUUUUCAAAUGUGACAGAUGACACUUACUAUUACCGUCGACGGCACCGACAUGAGAGGACACAGACUCAGAAGGAGGAGGAAGAAGAGAAACCUCAGACUACAUAUUCUGCAUUUAUUCAGCUACUUCCAGUUCUUGUGAUUGUGAUUAUAUCUGUCAUUACUCAGCUGCUGGCUACUAAUCCCCCAUAUAGUCUGUUCUAUAAAUCGACCUUGGGCUACACCAUUUCUAGAGAAACUCAGAACCUGCAGGUGCCUUACUUUGUGGAUAAAAACUUUGACAAGGCCUACAGAGGAGCUUCUCUGCAUGACUUGGAGAAAACAAUAGAGAAGGAUUACAUUGAUUAUAUCCAGACUAGUUGUUGGAAGGAGAAACAACAAAAGUCAGAGCUGACAAAUUUGGCAGGAUUAUACAGAGAUGAACGAUUGAAACAGAAAGCAGAGUCGCUGAAACUUGAAAACUGUGAGAAACUUUCCAAACUCAUUGGCCUACGCAGAGGUGGCUGAGAGGAUAAUGGUCCUACGCAGGGCUGGGGUUUUGCUACUUGUUCCUAUUUAUGUUCCUGAUUCCAUUUUAUAAUACAAAACUAGGUAAUGAUGAACACUUUACUAUUUGCUAACUUCGUUGGUUGGGCAGAGUGGCAGGAGCAUGGGCACGAGAGCCAGAUGUGUCUUCACAGGAUCCUUCCUGGGGAGUGGCUCCAGGGACCAGGAGUAGUUCAUCUAAGUUAAAUUAAUGGCAAGGCAUUGGAUUCCGUCUCCCUGCUCCAUGCCUACCCUGCCUAUGUGAAUGGAGUUCAGGGCAUCCCAGAGCAGAUCCAUGCUUUCUUCCUUCUUCCCUUCUUCAGUGAAGUCUUAAGAACCAGGCAUUCCUAGGCUUAGCCAAAGCUUAAUAUUAGUUAUUUACACUGUCUACCAAGAAUUAUACCUCUCCCUUCAUUAGAGUCAUCAUCUCCGCCAAGAUUUAGCCUUUGGAACAUGUUCCUGCCCAGCUUUCCAUUUUCUAGGGGAAUAUGGAGAAAUUUAAACUAUUGUAGUCAAUAGUUUUCUAUUAUUCCAAUCUCUGCUCAGUUAGUAGCAUUAGCAAACUGCCUAAUUUGAGAUUCCUUUAUUUCCUUAACCCUCUCUCCUUUAGAGAGUCCAGAAAUUAAAACUACUGAGCAGCAUCUGGAGGCGGGGGCCAGGGCGAAGGUAUAAUGCAAGACCGAGCCUCAUCUCCUCCACGAAGCCUCCCUACUCCAUCAUAGAACCCAGAGAAUGUCCCUUCGGUCAUUUCCCCUCAGUAUCAUCAUUGGUGUCAUCGCACUUAGGCUGAGUUCCUACAUCCCACAGAGGCAGAUGGUCAGACCCAGGAGGAGGCAUUGCCAGCUCUCCAGGCUGUUUGCUCAAGCCUAGAGAUAGAGGAGACAGAUCCUCUCUCCUUGGAUAUGGGGGUCUAGCUUUGGCCCCAGCAGCCACUUUGUUUAACCCAGUAUCCUAUAGUUUGUGAUUUGAGAUGAUUUUUCAUUCAUUCAACAUUUAUUGAGUGCCUACUAUAAAAGCAGGGGCUCUCACACAUAUUUUCUUACUUAAACCUCCUCACAACUCUGAAGUAGAUGUAUUAUCCCUGGUUCUAUGAAUGAGAACAUUGGCCCAGAGAGGAUGACCCAGGUCUUGUAGUGGCAGAGCAAGACGGUAGGCUGAGUGUCAAGUAGAAAGUGGGAGAGCAUCCUCAUGUCUCAGGUGAUUCUAGCCAGACUGGCAAAGCAGAACCUUUCCCGAGGAUGCCUCCGUCCUCCCCAACCCCAUGACCCCUCAUCUUUUCUGUGGCAAUCUUGCAUCUGUUCAGGACAACAUCCCUGCUGCUCUUUAGGAAGCAGGACCCUGUCUAACAUAAAUUCUGUACACAAAAUAAGAGGUCCCUCACAGGCAGGCAGCCCUCCACUGGUGACUAGGAAGAAUUCAGUCACUGCCUGGGCUGUGUGGUUCUGGGCCUUCCUGUGGAGCUGAGCUGCCUGAAUUAUCAUGACUCUGAACUUGGAAGGAUCAUUAAGUGACUGUAGCCUACACUCCAUGCUUCCUUCAUAUUGGAAGAAAAGUUUCUGGUAGAGAGUCGGCCGGGUGCACUGGCUCAAGCCUGUAAUCCCAGCACUUUGGGAGGCUGUGGCAGGUGGAUCACCUGAGGUCAGGAGUUCAAGACCAGCCUGGCCAACACAGUGAAACCCCAUCUCUACUAAUAAUACAAAAAUUAGCCAGGUGUGGUGGCACAUGCCUGUAGUCCCAGCUACUCGGGAGGCUGAGGCAUGAGAAUCGCUGCAACUUGCAAGGUGGAGGUUACAGUGAGCUGAAAUCACGCCACUGCACUCCACUCCAUCUCAAAAAAAAAAAGAGUCUACAUUAAACAGAUUCCAAAGUAAAGUUUCUUCAUCCCAAUGCAUGGCCAUGAUUUACACAGACGUGCCUAGCAUGGCUCAUCAACAUCUGAACGGUUGUUCCCUACCAUGCCUCUGCAGGCAUUCCACAGAGUCAGGAGAUGGGUUCACAGGUAAAGAUUGGGGGCUUUAGUGGCUUGUAGGGGACAACUGCUCAGUUGCAGGGAGAGGGAGCAUUUCUAGAAAUAGCCAGAUUUUGCUGCCCAACUAGAUCUGUCCUCCUGGUUUUAGGGGGCCCUUCUUGAUCCCCUCUGAGUGACUGAGGGAGGUUACAUUGUAAAAUAUGUCCAUGAGCCAAACAGGCUUAUGGAAAGUUCUUCUACACACAAAAAAAUCAAAGCUCUCCUCUCCCCAUCCCCAACCACUGCUAGAAAAUUGGCCAUAAUGAAACUGACUUGACAGGUUAAAAGACCCUGUCCUAGAUGCCCAGGAAUCAGGUAGUCACACAUUUUAUGGACUUCAUGGCAGCGAUAAGUAAUCUGUGAUGAUACUAAAUAGAAGCAAUAAUAACUAACUCCAUUAAAUGUCACGCUGAUUGUCUGUUUUUAUAGCACCGAUGGUACUGUUUUAUUUAUUGCCAAUAGACCACAACAUUCACAUCUGUUUUUCCUCAAGGGAACCGUAUUUGCUUUUGGUUGAAGGAUUUAUCUAUUUGAUACUAUCCAGAAUAUUGUGAAGCUAUAAUUUCCUGGGUUAUAUUUUAGAUGGGUUGUCUGCAUGGUGGUAAAAUAAGCUUUUUCCUCUCGCCUACGUCCUUUGGAAGAUCUCCUGAUCAUACAUAACUAGGUAGGGCUUAUUCUUGCUGCCGGAGCUUGGCACCCAGCUCUAGACUGUUUCUUUGAGCAUUACUGCAGAUUGGAGACGUGUGUGAGAGGAGCAGCGCUCAGAAAUAGGGCUUGAGGCUCAAGCAGAAACUGAAGCUCUCAUUCAAAUGAAGAUGCUCUCUCUACCGCACGAUCGGCAGUGAGAAAAGGAGGAUGAAAAUCCUUCUCAUCACAAAGAGCUUGAAGGAACCCACGUCCCCAGAUUAGCAACCCUAGAGUUCAUCUGCUCAGGCCGGGAAAUGUGUAAGCUUCCUUGAUCAGCUCCAGGCCUCACAGCACGGGAGCAGUGACCAGUAAGGAAACGUCACUGCUGUGCUUUCUGUUGGAAAUUGUUCGAAAAUACAGUGAACUGGCCAGGCCCAGUAGCUCAUGCCUGUAAUCCCAGCACUUUGAAAGGCUGAGGCAGGCAGAUCAUUUGAGGUCAGGAGUUCCAGACCAGCCUGGCCAACAUGGUGAAACCCUGUCUGUACUAAAAAUACAAAAAUUAGGCGGGCAUGGUAGCACGUGUCUGUAAUCCCAGCUCCUCAGGAGGCUGAGGCAGAAGAAUCUCUUGAGCCUGGGAGGCAGAGGUUGCAGUAAGCUGAGAUCACAUCAUUGCACUCCAGCCUGGGUGACAGAGCAAGACUCUGUCUCAAAAAAAAAAAAAGAAAGAAAAAAGAAAAUACAGUGAACUCCAGAUGCCACUGGAACAUGGGUUCCAGCAGCCUGGCCAAGCUAUGUGUCAUUCUUUUUCCUCAUGAUACCCAGGAUGGGCUUUGUGAGGAGGCACUGUGCCGUUCCAGUGGCUUUCUGUUACAGCUGGCCACACCAUACAAGCAAGUACAUCAUCUGCAUGCACUGCUCCUCACAGGAGCUUGCACUUCAUUCAUAUUUAUUCUGCCCUCAUUUAAGGUAUAAGCUUAGUGUCCUAAUAUAUUUAUUUUUGGAAAGGGCCAAGUUACAAAACAUCUUUUUUUUGAGGCUGCACUGUUGAUAUGUCAUGCAGUGGCCACCAAGAAAGUAUAUACUCGUGUUAGAUACUGAUUACAUCAUUUACAUCACGCUCAGUAUUUGGAAUUAAAGAUGUGAAUGUUCUGUGACCAGAGUAGGGAUGACACAAAUGGAAUCAGCUCCUGGUGGACUAAGAAUCUUGAAAAAAUCUGGCCACCUCAUCCACUACAUCUGGAUUGAGUGUACUGCAACAAAGAAAAACAUUAAACAAUUUUAUAUUAAAAGAA